GGUCCCGUCCCGUCCCGUCCUGUGCGGCCCCGUCCCGCCGCCCGCCCGCCAGCCAUGAGCUCCACGCAGUUCAACAAGGGCCCCUCGUACGGGCUGUCGGCCGAGGUCAAGAACCGGCUCCUGUCCAAAUAUGACCCCCAGAAGGAGGCAGAGCUCCGCACCUGGAUCGAGGGACUCACCGGCCUCUCCAUCGGCCCCGACUUCCAGAAGGGCCUGAAGGAUGGAACUAUCUUAUGCACACUCAUGAACAAGCUACAGCCGGGCUCCGUCCCCAAGAUCAACCGCUCCAUGCAGAACUGGCACCAGCUAGAAAACCUGUCCAACUUCAUCAAGGCCAUGGUCAGCUACGGCAUGAACCCUGUGGACCUGUUCGAGGCCAACGACCUGUUUGAGAGUGGGAACAUGACGCAGGUGCAGGUGUCUCUUCUCGCCCUGGCGGGGAAGGGCCUAGAUCUAGGGUCCCUGGCUGCCCUCUGCUGGUACUCCCGGCCCCUUUCCCUCACCCAGGCCAAGACUAAGGGGCUGCAGAGCGGGGUGGACAUUGGCGUCAAGUACUCGGAGAAGCAGGAGCGGAAUUUCGACGAUGCCACCAUGAAGGCUGGCCAGUGCGUCAUCGGGCUGCAGAUGGGCACCAACAAAUGCGCCAGCCAGUCGGGCAUGACUGCCUACGGCACGAGAAGGCAUCUCUAUGACCCCAAGAACCAUAUCCUGCCCCCCAUGGACCACUCGACCAUCAGCCUCCAGAUGGGCACGAACAAGUGUGCCAGCCAGGUGGGCAUGACGGCUCCCGGGACCCGGCGGCACAUCUAUGAUACCAAGCUGGGAACCGACAAGUGUGACAACUCCUCCAUGUCCCUGCAGAUGGGCUACACGCAGGGCGCCAACCAGAGCGGCCAGGUCUUCGGCCUGGGCCGGCAGAUAUAUGACCCCAAGUACUGCCCGCAAGGCACAGUGGCCGAUGGGGCUCCCUCGGGCACCGGCGACUGCCCGGACCCGGGGGAGGUCCCUGAAUAUCCCCCUUACUACCAGGAGGAGGCCGGCUACUGAGGCUCCCAGCACGCUCUCUCCCCACAUCGUCUGCCCAUCUGGGUUUUUGGGUUUUUCUGUGUUUUCAUCUUUUUUUUUUUUUUCUUAACCCGUUCAGUGCUGCCAGUCAACCAAGGGUCUGUGAGUGUCAGCGUGGGAUCAGGCAGCAGAGCUUUUUUCCCCUUUGCCUUGAUCCUUCGCAAGGCUGAGCCACUGGGCUGUGGGGGAAGGGGUCAAGGCCAUAUCCCAAUACGUGUAGGGCGAGGGUCCCUGCUGGCACAUUCAGGCUGUGCUGGGAAGAAGAGACCUGGGCUUGGAAGGAACCGGUCCCCGACGGUUUCUGCUUGCCUCGCCUCUUCCCCCUUUUGUCAGCUGAGCAGUUUGUGGUUUCUAUGCCCGCAAGUUUCAGGAAGUAUUCACAAAAGAAAAAUACAUUUUUUCCCCCAGGGGUGGGGCAAGGACAGUGGAGAGAGUGCUAGGAAAUGAGUCCCCUGGGAAAGGGGACCGGGCCGUGAUGUUAAAUAUCUCCGGCUCCCAAGUGACUGGAUUUGCCUAGGACCUUCAGACCAACAGACUUCAGACCCUCAGACCUGCCCCGGGGCCAGGUGGAGAAAGUGAGGGCCGUACAAGGAAGUGAAAUUCUGAGUUGUUGGGGCUAAGCCUGACCCCCUCUCCAUGCUCCCCGCCCCAACCCACUCUGGCCUCAGUAGAUUUUUUUUUCAGUUGUGGUUGUUGCCCAGGCUGGAGUGCAGUGGCGCCAUCUUGGCUCACUGCACCUCCACCUUCCGGGCUCAAGCGAUUCUCCAGCCUCAGCCUCCUGAGUAGCUAGGACUGCAGGUGCUCCACCACGCCCGGCUAAUUUUUGUAUUUUUAGUAGAGAUGGGGUUUCCCCAUGUUGGCCAGGCUGGUCUCGAACUCCUGGCCUCAGGUGUGAUCCGCCCGCCUCCGCCUCCCCAAGCGCUGAGAUUACAGGUGUGAGCCACCGUGCCCAGCCCCUCAGUAGGUUUUAAGGAGCCCCCAGCCCUCCUCCCUUCUGGGCCCGACCAGCUUAUACUGCUCCAUCUUCCCCGGCCACAUGCCCCGCCAAGUACUGCACAGGGACCCCCCACCCAGGGGACCUGCUCCGUGAGAUAAUGUGAAAUACGACUGUGGACCAAACGCAAUAAAACCUCUGUUUGUACGAAGA